AGAAGAACAAAAGCAUUUGGAAGUAACAGGACCUCUUUCUAGCUCUCAGAAAAGUCUGAGAAGAAAGGAGCCCUGCGUUCCCCUAAGCUGUGCAGCAGAUACUGUGAUGAUGGAUUGCAAGUGCAAAGAGUAAGACAAAACUCCAGCACAUAAAGGACAAUGACAACCAGAAAGCUUCAGCCCGAUCCUGCCCUUUCCUUGAACGGGACUGGAUCCUAGGAGGUGAAGCCAUUUCCAAUUUUUUGUCCUCUGCCUCCCUCUGCUGUUCUUCUAGAGAAGUUUUUCCUUACAACAAUGAGAAAACAUGUACUAGCUGCAUCCUUUUCUAUGCUCUCCCUGCUGGUGAUAAUGGGAGAUACAGACAGUAAAACGGACAGCUCAUUCAUAAUGGACUCGGACCCUCGACGCUGCAUGAGGCACCACUAUGUGGAUUCUAUCAGUCACCCAUUGUACAAGUGUAGCUCAAAGAUGGUGCUCCUGGCCAGGUGCGAGGGGCACUGCAGCCAGGCGUCACGCUCCGAGCCUUUGGUGUCGUUCAGCACUGUCCUCAAGCAACCCUUCCGUUCCUCCUGUCACUGCUGCCGGCCCCAGACUUCCAAGCUGAAGGCACUGCGGCUGCGAUGCUCAGGGGGCAUGCGACUCACUGCCACCUACCGGUACAUCCUCUCCUGUCACUGCGAGGAAUGCAAUUCCUGAGGCCCGCUGCUGUGUGUGGCUUCUGGAUGGGACAACUGUAGAGGCAGUUCGACCAGCCAGGGAAAGACUGGCAAGAAAAGAGUUAAGGCAAAAAAGGAUGCAACAAUUCUCCCGGGACUCUGCAUAUUCUAGUAAUAAAGACUCUACAUGCUUGUUGACAGAGAGAGAUACUCUGGGAACUUCUUUGCAGUUCCCAUCUCCUUUCUCUGGUACAAUUUCUUUUGGUUCAUUUUCAGAUUCAGGCAUUUUCCCCCUUGGCUCUCAAUGCUGUUUGGGUUUCCAACAAUUCAGCAUUAGUGGGAAAAAGUGGGCCCUCAUACACAAGCGUGUCAGGCUGUCAGUGUUUGGUGCACGCUGGGGAAGAAUUUACUUUGGAAAGUAGAAAAGCCCAGCUUUUCCUGGGACAUCUUCUGUUAUUGUUGAUGUUUUUUUUUACCUUGUCAUUUUGGUCUAAGGUUGCCAUUGCUGCUAAAGGUUACCGAUUUCAAAGUCCAGAUACCAAGCAUGUGGAUAUGUUUAGCUACGUUUACUCACAGCCAGCGAACUGACAUUAAAAUAACUAACAAACAGAUUCUUUUAUGUGAUGCUGGAACUCUUGACAGCUAUAAUUAUUAUUCAGAAAUGACUUUUUGAAAGUAAAAGCAGCAUAAAGAAUUUGUCACAGGAAGGCUGUCUCAGAUAAAUUAUGGUAAAAUUUUGUAAGGGAGCAGACUUUUAAAGACUUGCACAAAUACGGAUCCUGCACUGACUCUGGAAAAGGCAUAUAUGUACUAGUGGCAUGGAGAAUGCACCAUACUCAUGCAUGCAAAUUAGACAACCAAGUAUGAAUCUAUUUGUGGGUGUGCUAUAGCUUUAGCCGUGUCACGGGCAUCAUUCUCUAAUAUCCACUUGUCCAUGUGAAACAUGUUGCCAAAAUGGUGGCCUGGCUUGUCUUCUGAACGUUUGGUUCAAAUGUGUUUUGGUCCUGGAGGCUCAAAUUUUGAGUUAUUCCCACGUUUUGAAAUAAAAAGAGUAUAUUCAAAA